GUGCGUACGUGCUCGCUCACGGCGGCGGCGGCGGAGCGGAGAGGCCAGAGCCGGAGACCGAGCUGGGAUCGGGCCCCGGGCGGGGGCGGUGCGAGCGGCGCCAAGCAGAUCUUAGGGGCGGGGACGGAGCCGGGGCGGGCGGGACUGAAGCGGAGCCCGGGAACGGGGCGGGAGGUCCCAGGGUCCCGGGUUGGGGGGGUGGAGCAGCAUUUCGUCGCCGCGGGGGUGCCGGGACUCCGGCCGCAGUGUCGCCGCCAUCACGGACUUCCUGUGGGACAAGCGCACGGGCCUCGCCGCCAGAACGAUGCCGCAUCCUCGAAGGUACCACUCCUCAGAGCGAGGCAGCCGGGGGAGUUACCGUGAACACUAUCGGAGCCGAAAGCAUAAGCGACGAAGAAGUCGCUCCUGGUCAAGUAGUAGUGACCGGACACGACGGCGUCGGCGAGAGGACAGCUACCAUGUCCGUUCUCGAAGCAGUUAUGAUGAUCGUUCGUCCGACCGGAGGGUGUAUGACCGGCGAUACUGUGGCAGCUACAGACGCAACGAUUAUAGCCGGGAUCGGGGAGAUGCCUACUAUGACACAGACUAUCGGCAUUCCUAUGAAUAUCAGCGGGAGAACAGCAGUUACCGCAGCCAGCGCAGCAGCCGGAGGAAGCACAGACGGCGGAGGAGGCGCAGCCGGACAUUUAGCCGCUCAUCUUCGCAGCACAGCAGCCGGAGAGCCAAGAGUGUAGAGGACGACGCUGAGGGCCACCUCAUCUACCACGUCGGGGACUGGCUACAAGAGCGAUAUGAAAUCGUUAGCACCUUAGGAGAGGGGACCUUCGGCCGAGUUGUACAAUGUGUUGACCAUCGCAGGGGUGGGGCUCGAGUUGCCCUGAAGAUCAUUAAGAAUGUGGAGAAGUACAAGGAAGCAGCUCGACUUGAGAUCAACGUGCUAGAGAAAAUCAAUGAGAAAGACCCUGACAACAAGAACCUCUGUGUCCAGAUGUUUGACUGGUUUGACUACCAUGGCCACAUGUGUAUCUCCUUUGAGCUUCUGGGCCUUAGCACCUUCGAUUUCCUCAAAGACAACAACUACCUGCCCUACCCCAUCCACCAAGUGCGCCACAUGGCCUUCCAGCUGUGCCAGGCUGUCAAGUUCCUCCAUGAUAACAAGCUGACACAUACAGACCUCAAGCCUGAAAAUAUUCUGUUUGUGAAUUCAGACUAUGAGCUCACCUACAACCUAGAGAAGAAGCGAGAUGAGCGCAGUGUGAAGAGCACAGCUGUGCGGGUGGUAGACUUUGGCAGUGCCACCUUUGACCAUGAGCACCAUAGCACCAUUGUCUCCACUCGCCAUUACCGAGCACCAGAAGUCAUCCUUGAGUUGGGCUGGUCACAGCCUUGUGAUGUGUGGAGUAUAGGCUGCAUCAUCUUUGAAUACUAUGUGGGAUUCACCCUCUUCCAGACCCAUGACAACAGAGAGCAUCUAGCCAUGAUGGAAAGGAUCUUGGGUCCUAUCCCUUCCCGGAUGAUCCGAAAGACAAGAAAGCAGAAAUAUUUUUACCGGGGUCGCCUGGAUUGGGAUGAGAACACAUCAGCUGGGCGCUAUGUUCGUGAGAACUGCAAACCGCUGCGGCGGUAUCUGACCUCAGAGGCAGAGGAACACCACCAGCUCUUCGAUCUGAUUGAAAGCAUGCUAGAGUAUGAACCAGCUAAGCGGCUGACCUUGGGUGAAGCCCUUCAGCAUCCUUUCUUCGCCCGCCUUCGGGCUGAGCCGCCCAACAAGUUGUGGGACUCCAGUCGGGAUAUCAGUCGGUGACGAUCAGGCCCUGGGCCCCCCUGCAUCUUUUAUAGCAGUGGGUGUCCAGUCCAGGACACUGGUGCUUUUUUAUACAAGAGAACGAGCCAGAGUUCACUCCUUCCUCCUGGCUCUCUAUAUACCUGUGAAUAUGUGAAAUAGUGUAAAUAUGAAAGAACUUGUACCUAUCACUUCAACCCCUGCCUUGUACAUAAUACUAUUCCAUCCACACAGUUUCCACCCUCACCUGCCCCCUCAUACGGAGUUGGAUGGGGGCCGAGUGAGGUAACCAGGUGGCAUCUACCCCAUGUUUUAUAAGGAAUUUUGUACAGUCUUUGUGAAAUAAAAUAACGUGCUUCAUUUGACCCCCA